AGGUCCCCAAGGCCUUGGGGGCAAAUAUUUGUGACACAGUUUGGUGCUAGGACUUAGUUUCUAGAUGUGACCUUAUCUCUGCUAUCUAUGAGUUUUCUUAAUAGGUUGGGUAAAAAAGUAACAUUUAAAAUCUUCAAGGAAAUAUACUCUCGACACUCCUACUGUUGUUUUCAGGUUUGUUUCUAUUAAUUAAGUGCUAAGCGGGAGCAUUAUUGGAGUUCGUUAAUUUCAGCAAAAGAUCCUUCAGUAAAUGAAUCACUCAGAUGCCUCUGUAUUUAGGAUUCAAAAAAAUCAGACUGCUGGAGUCACCUUCAUCCUCUUGGGCUUCUCAGAAUUUCCAGACCUUCAGAUACCCCUGUUCCUGGUCUUCCUGACCAUCUACACAAUCACUGUGAUGGGGAAUCUGGGCAUGAUCAUGGUCAUCAGGAUCAACCCCAAACUCCACACCCCUAUGUACUUUUUCCUCAGCCACUUGUCCUUUGUUGAUUUCUGUUAUUCCACCACAAUUACACCAAAACUGCUGGAGAACUUGGUUGUGGAAGACAGAAUCAUCUCCUUCACAGGAUGCAUCAUGCAAUUCUUCUUUGCCUGUAUAUUUGUGGUGACAGAAACAUUCAUGCUGGCAGCGAUGGCUUAUGACAGAUUUGUGGCAGUGUGUAACCCUCUGCUUUACACAGUUGCAAUGUCCCAGAGGCUUUGCUCCUUGUUAGUGGCUGCAUCAUACUCUUGGAGUUUAGUUUGUUCCUUAACAUACACAUAUUUUCUGUUGACUUUAUCUUUUUGUAGGACUAACUUCAUUAAUAACUUUGUCUGUGAGCACGCUGCCAUUGUUGCUGUGUCCUGCUCUGACCCCUACAUGAGCCAGAAGGUCAUUUUAGUUUCUGCAACAUUCAAUGAAAUAAGCAGCCUGGUGAUCAUUCUCACUUCCUAUGCUUUCAUUUUUAUCACUGUCAUGAAGAUGCCUUCCACUGGGGGGCGCAAGAAAGCGUUCUCCACGUGUGCCUCCCACCUGACCGCCAUUACCAUUUUCCAUGGGACUAUCCUUUUUCUCUACUGUGUUCCUAACUCCAAAAGUUCAUGGCUCAUGGUCAAGGUGGCCUCUGUCUUUUACACAGUGGUCAUUCCCAUGCUGAACCCCUUGAUCUAUAGCCUCAGGAACAAAGAUGUAAAAGAGACAGUCAGGAAGUUAGUCAUUACCAAAUUAUUAUGUCAUAAAAUGUAAUGCUAGAAAUAUUAAUUAUUUAUCCUUGAGAGCAGCACUGCAGUUGUUCAAUAACUAGUCAUUGCAUGAAAUUAUGAUAACCCUCCAACUGACAGUACAAUAUCUAUUCACACUGAUGUUUAGUAAAAUAACUUUAAAGUUAUAAAUACUGUAAGUAUGGAAUCUCAGACCAUUUAAACUAAAUUUUUGAUCGAGAAUAUUGUAAUACAAAAGUUUUUGUGUUAGUAUACGUUUAUUGUGAUUGUCCAGGUCAAAUUUCAGUUCAAUUUAAAUCUUGCAAAAUGUAAAAAUUUUUGAGAUGAUCUGAAGAAUAGUAGUUUAUAAUGAGGAAGUUUACCUGAUAACAUAAAAUUACUAUGAUAAGAGCUGUUCAGUAUAAAACACUAUCUAUAAAAUAAUUACAAUUAAUUCUGUAUGGGCAACUUUGGCAUUAGAAGAUUUACAGACAAACAAAAAUAAAUAAGAAAAUUAUCUUCCUUACGAAGUCCAGAAUCUGGUAAAGUUAAGUUAUACUUGGUAUUAUAAAUUAUAUUUUUCUUUAUGCAUGAUAAUAAGAAGAUGGUAAAUAUUUUUGCAAAUAAAUGCCCAUCACCCUAGUUCUGCCACUGAUGCCAAUAUGAUUGUGCAUGUUAUUUAUUUAUUAAAAAUUUUAUUGAGAUAAUUUUCUAUUCAUUUUCCUUUGUAAGAAAUAAUAUAGAGGAAUUCCAAUUAUCUUUUAACCAGUUUCCCCCUAAGAUAGUACAAUAUAACAACCAGGAUAAUGAUAUUGAGAUAAUACACAUACAUUAUUCAAGCAUUAGUUAUGUAUUGAUAAAAGAAAUAUUCAUAAACUCAGUGAUAUCUAACAGUAAGCAAUCCUUUCAAAUAAGUGACUUGACUGGGGUAGCUCUGUUGAUAUCAGUUCGACCAUUUGGGUGUCAAGAAUGGGGUAACUAGAUCAGCUACCUUUGGAACUAGAGACCUGUAUGUAUGUCAUCUUCUUUGGACUCUUUGGCUGAUAGUCUUUGUUGAAAGCAGAGCCACAAUAGAGUAUUCCAAAAAUAAAAGCAUACUUAACGUUCCUGUUUGGGUCUCACCUGUUAACAUUUUAUGAGUCAGAGAAAAUCACGUCCAAGCCCCAAAGCAAGAGUUGAGAAAGUUAUCUAUUUCUUGUAGAACUGCAAGAUUACAAGUCAAGAGUGAUGGGUACAGGGAGAAAUGAAAAACUGGGUUCAAAAUUGAUUGAAACAUUUACAUCUUUAAACACAUUCUUCCUUGAUAAUGCCAGAUAACUUUACUGCAGAAAACAGAUAACCCAUGGCUCUAAUUGGUUUUAGAGAAGUUUUCAAAUAAUUGAAAUAAUUUGAUUGCCUUAACCAAAUGGCUGGUUGAGAUUAAGUAUAAGAACUUACAUUUUCUCCUUGUGUCUUGCCAGUCAUGAUUAAGGCUUACAAGCACAGAAUAUGAAGUCAACCAUGUGUUGAAGGUCCAAUCCAAGCUGUUAAGUGAUACUUGUUUCCCCUCAAGGUUUAUCUUUAUUUCCAAAUAAAAAUUCAAUAACUUUUUACCUUAAUGCUUUACACCAACUUACAUGUCUAUGCAACUUACUGUUUAGGAAUAUACAACAAAAUUCUCAACACUUACAGAAUACAGCAAAAGUAACAGAGGAUUUACUUUAAUUUUUAACUGUAGAUAAUGAGUCAUAAUUAAAUGCUCUAGUCGAGUAUUUUUAAAGCUGUGUGUAUGUGUGUGCAUAUGUGUAUAGUUUAAUAAAGAUGUUAAGGAGCACAAAAAAGGAUUUAGAAAGUUUGAGUAUGCAUCGCAGAAUAUUUAGUAUAUUCAAUAAGGUUUCCAGGAUAAAGUUAGAAUAUACUAUUUUUAAAUAUUGUUUUGGAAGAUGUAAGCUGUAAUUUGGUAGGUUUCUUUUAGUACAAAAUAAAAAUCAAAGAAAAAAAGAAUAGUUGCUAAUCCCUUUAAUACAAGAUUUUUUUAUUUUGGUAAAUGUUCAUAAAUGGGCAGUUUACACAAAUAUAAUGCAAUUUCCCCCCCAAAUUCUCAAAUUAUACUUUCAGUGUGAAAGCAAACAUGUUAACUGUGAAGAUAAAUACAUUUUAGAUAAUGUAAGUGAGUUUGCUAAUGGUCAUAUUAAGUGAUAGCUAUGGGCUAUUUUUUUUCUACAAAUACAUUUGUAUGCUGCUCUUCUUUUAAACUUUUGGAUACAGUAGGUAUAAAUGUGACUUUUUUCCCAUGGAGGGCUGUGGCAGGACAUUUGCUAUCAUAUGCACAAUACUAAAGCAAGUUAUAUAGUUUAAUGCUCACUUCUUAGUGGAUUAACAACUAUAAAAAUUAUAUCUGGACCAUUUUAUGUAAAUGUCAACUUUCAUAUUAUGUUGACUAAACAAAGACGGCAUCAAAGAUUGUAUUAGUGUUGGACAAAUAUAUCAUUACGUGAUUAUAUUACAUAACACUUUGCUUACGUGAGUG